GGGGAUGUGAUGGAAGAUUAGAUAUGUUAAAGUUGGCAAAGAAGCGUCUGAGGAGGUGACUUUAAAAAAGAAUACGUGUGACAGCUUUAUUGAAGUAUAAAAUAACAUUAAUUUCAACCAUUGAAAGUGUAUAUUGUGAGUUUGGAAAUUUUAUGCAGUUGCGUAAACAUGGCAAGUUCAAAUUUGGGACAUUUUCAUCACCCCAAGAAGUUCGGAGGAGGCAACUUUUGAACUGGGAUAUGAAGAUUCAAACGGAGGUAGCUGUGGGGAGGGAGAAGCAAAUCAUCCCAAGCUGAAGGAACAGCACUAGGUUUGCUCCAAGGCAGGGAUGAGCUUGUUGUGUUCAGCGGAGAAAGGAAGCCAGCAGAGCUAGGAGGGCUGGGGUGCAGCAAGGCGGGAGAGAGCGGGAAGAGAUUAGGUGGGUCCCACAGAUGACUGUGCCUUCUGAACUUUGGAAGCUUCCCAGUGCUCAGCAUAAGGUGUGGUCCACACUGACUAACACGAACGAUUCUCACCUACCAUGUUCUUUUUCCUAAGUUCAUCCCUAAUGGCAGAAAUGUUCUCUCCCAACUUGAAGGUUGAGGUAGAGGAAUAGAGUGAAAGUAAUAUUUAUUAAGAACCUGUAGUGCUUUAGGCAGUGUGUGUGUGUGGCUUCAUUUAGUUCUCAUAACUCUGUGAAGUAGAUAUUAGUGUCUCUGUUUUACAGAUGAGAAAAUCAAGGUUAAGUGACCCGUCCAAAGCCGUGUAACCAGCACCUGGACUGAUUGCAGAAGCCUUGUCAUGCCUUUGUUCGUUCAUACAGCCAACUGGUGUUUCAAGUACCUCUGCAUUUGAGGGCAGAAGUGUGGCCGGCAAGGACCACAUCCCCUCACGUUCACUAAAAUGUACAUGUGCUUGUAGCUGUUGCUCUGACCUUUUGUUCUGCACUUAUUUUUCAUGAAGCUGAGGAAACUCAAAUGCCUUCCCCAAAUUCCUUGCAGUUUCUCCGUUCUGUGUUGUCUUGUUAGCAAGGAUGUCACUCAGCCAUUUGGCUCCCUUUGGAGAGGUGACUGGUAUGGAGGACUUUUCAGCGUAACAGGUUCAAAAUGAGCCUGUUUGGAACAACCUCAGGUUUUGGAACCAGUGGGACCAGCAUGUUUGGCAGUGCAACUACAGACAAUCACAAUCCCAUGAAGGAUAUUGAAGUAACAUCAUCUCCUGAUGAUAGCAUUGGUUGUCUGUCUUUUAGCCCACCAACCUUGCCGGGGAACUUUCUUAUUGCAGGAUCAUGGGCUAAUGAUGUUCGCUGCUGGGAAGUUCAAGACAGUGGACAGACCAUUCCAAAAGCCCAGCAGAUGCACACUGGGCCUGUGCUUGAUGUCUGCUGGAGUGACGAUGGGAGCAAAGUGUUUACGGCAUCGUGUGAUAAAACUGCCAAAAUGUGGGACCUCAGCAGUAACCAAGCGAUACAGAUCGCACAGCAUGAUGCUCCUGUUAAAACCAUCCAUUGGAUCAAAGCUCCAAACUACAGCUGUGUGAUGACUGGGAGCUGGGAUAAGACUUUAAAGUUUUGGGAUACUCGAUCGUCAAAUCCUAUGAUGGUUUUGCAACUCCCUGAAAGGUGUUACUGUGCUGACGUGAUAUACCCCAUGGCUGUGGUGGCAACUGCAGAGAGGGGCCUGAUUGUCUAUCAGCUAGAGAAUCAACCUUCUGAAUUCAGGAGGAUAGAAUCUCCACUGAAACAUCAGCAUCGGUGUGUGGCUAUUUUUAAAGACAAACAGAACAAGCCUACUGGUUUUGCCCUGGGAAGUAUCGAGGGGAGAGUUGCUAUUCACUAUAUCAACCCCCCGAACCCCGCCAAAGAUAACUUCACCUUUAAAUGUCAUCGAUCUAAUGGAACCAACACUUCAGCUCCUCAGGACAUUUAUGCGGUAAAUGGAAUCGCGUUCCAUCCUGUUCAUGGCACCCUUGCAACUGUGGGAUCUGAUGGUAGAUUCAGCUUCUGGGACAAAGAUGCCAGAACAAAACUAAAAACUUCGGAACAGUUAGAUCAGCCCAUCUCAGCUUGCUGUUUCAAUCACAAUGGAAACAUAUUUGCAUACGCUUCCAGCUACGACUGGUCAAAGGGACAUGAAUUUUAUAAUCCCCAGAAAAAAAAUUACAUUUUCCUGCGUAAUGCAGCCGAAGAGCUAAAGCCCAGGAAUAAGAAGUAGUGGCUGGAGACUCUGGCUCAGCCAGAGUUGUUUCUCUCCACUCUGCCUCAUCUCUGUACGAAUUUGGGUCCCAGCCUUGUUGGGUUGUCAGCCAUGGACAUGGAUUUCAACCCCUGGAGAAAACGAUGUCAUUGUUCAGCAGCUGAGAGCCCAGGCGUCCGCGGCGACUUGCCGUCUCUCCAUUCCACUGCCUGUUGCAGAGUUUUUCUGUAACUAAGGGGGUUGAGGUUAUUGUAGACGUUAGAUUGCGGGCACCGCCAGGGAUUUUGCAGCGCUUCAGUGUACGUGUUAGAGAAUAUUGGAAAAGCGUCUGUGAGCCCCGUGCUGUAUUUUGUAAUAAAGUCUUUUGCAGAUUGCUUCCCGAGCUUCCUUUGUCCUUUUCUCCCCUUGCCCACCCCGUAACCUCAGGAACAUGCGUCCUGCCCAGCAUCAGCGUGGGGUUUUGAGUUGAGAUUUCAGACACCCUCUGGGAAAUGCGGCAACCUUAGGGGAAAGGGAGUCCCCAGCUGCGCUCACUUCUGCUGCGCGGAACGGCAGCCUCUGUGAGCCCUGGUGGGCAGAGUUUGAAUGUGUUUUUCCUUGCUUCCCUCAUUCCCAUCUUCAAAAUCCCCAGUGCUUUCUGGCCUUGCUGCUCAGAUUUCCGAGUGACUCAAAUGGGGACUGUUACUUGUGCUGGGUGACAGGCCAUUUGUGGGUAACCUCCUAAGGCCCAAGUGGGUGACACUUGCGUGACUUUCAAGUUAGAACCCAAGCCCCCUGCAUGGGAAUUGCCCUGAACUCUUACCCACCCCGGUCCCCUGCAUGGGAAUUGCCCUGAACCCUCAGUAGUGGUUGUUUGGCUGUUCUUUUGUAUUUUGUGUAAUUUAAAAUUCCUGGUUGGUAAGUAUUCAAAAUGAAAUUCAGCUGGGCUGAGAAAAAGUGUGACUUUUGGGUCUGUCACUGUAUUUCUCACCUGUGAUCUCAAAUGCUUCUUAGGCCUUUCUGUUUGGACUAAUGUGUGAAGUCUGACUUGCUGAGUGUAAAAUUCUAGUAUCGAUAGUGUUGUAAGAUGUGUUUGCCUACUCAUAAAAAACAAUGAAAAUAAAAUUUUCUACUGGAAGAGA